AGACAGCAUCUCUCUCUGUCACUUAGGCUGGAAUGAAGUGGUGUGAUCACUGCAGCCUCCAACUCCAGGGCUCAGGUGAUCCUCCUGUUUCAGCCUCCCAAGUAGCUGGGAUUACAAGCAUGUACCACCACAUCUGGCUAAUUUUUUUUAUAGAGAUGGGGUCUUAUUUUGUUGCUUAGGCUGUUCUGGAGCUCUGGCCUCAAGUGAUCUUCCUAUCUUGGCCUCCCAAAAUACUGAGAUUACAGAUGUGAGCCGCCACACCCAGCACUGAAUAGUGCUUUUGAUGUUGCCACUGACCUAUUCAGUUGAGACCGCAUUGGGUUGUAAUUUGUGGUGUUCCUCCCUCUCCAUCUGAAUUUUCAGAAGCUGUUAAGGACAGCCCAGUAGAUGCUCAGAUGUCAUAGGUAAAGGUCAUACAUUGAACUCUUUGUCUUUCCUCCAGUUCUGCUUCCCCCUUGGAGUCCCUGUCUCAGUUAAUGGCACCAGGGAUCAUCAUUGCCUUGUGAUUCUGACUCCUUCUCUUUCACCUCCACCCUACCUGCAUCAGUUACGAAAAGUCCAGCUGCUGCUCCCUCCUAUGUCUUUCUCCUAUCUGCCCUCUCCUCUCCAUCCCUUCUACUGCUGCCUUAGCUCAGGUCACCACUGUCUUUCACUCAGACCAUUGGACUUGCCUUGAACAUGAAUUCCCACCACCAGCUUCUCUCCUCUUAUAAUCCCAACAGUUAUGUAUCGGGAUCUGACAUGUAGGUAUGACCUUGUAACUUUCCUGAUUGAAACCCCUCAGUGGCUCCCCAUUGCCCUGGGAUAAGGACCAGCCUGCCAGCAUGUCGUGAGGCCAUUAUUGAUUGGAUGCACUUUCCUCUGCAGUCCUAUUUCUGACUUGUCUCAUUUACACAGCUUACAUUUGAUCAUCUGUAACCCCUAUACAUCUUCUGUGCAUUUGCACACUCCCCGUCUCUGUGUAGAUGCCCCCCCUCCCCAGGUCCACUUGGAAAACCAUCACCUGAAUUUCUAGGCAUUGUACAAACGUUCCCUCUUUUGUGGAGCUUUCGUCUCCUUCCCUCCAGAAGACCAAGAGGAGUAAAGGUGUUAUCAUAGAAUAACUGUUGGGAUAGAGAUAUAGGCUUCAUCUAUUUUCUAAUGCCUCCUCAGAUUCAGAGUCUUCCAAAGUUUCCCUGCAGACUGAGCAAUGAAUAAUUAAGCAAACAAGUCUCUAAAACAUCUUGAAAUGCUUAUGUAUGCUAAAUAUGUAGUUUUGAGUUCUUGUUUUGGUUUUGCUGGAGCUUUUGCCUUCUUCCUCCAUUACAAUGGAUGAUGAGAAUCAACAAUGUAGAAUUAUUCUCGGUUAGUUUAUAUCUUGUUUUUAACCUGGUAUCUUCAGUGUGUUAAGACAUUUUUCCUUUCUUGUGGGGGUUCCCCUGCAAAGAAGGAGGCUCACUUGUGGGGCCGAUGACCACUGUCUCUAGGCAACCCAGAGAGGUGUGAAAGAAAGAAGGGGGCUGUGAGGCUGCAGGGAGUAUAUUCCCCAUCUCCAGCCAGGGUCACACCUGUCACUUCUGUUUAGUACCUCUUCCUAGUAAGGAGAACGUAUGCUCCCUUUCUGGAAGGGUCUACUUAGCAGAAACGAGGAGUGGCGAGCUCAUGUGGAAAGUGCUUUUUUGAUGUGUUCUUUCAUGUAGGGGACACACGGUGUGGAGGGGAUGCACAAUUACUCUUCUGUGGUUCCUCUUUCUUACUCCAGGGUCUCCUUUGCCAUGAGGUCCCUAGGGACGUCUUAUCAGAGGAGAAGAAAAGUACCUUCUUAGUUCUUUUUUGUUUUGUUUUGUUUUGUUUUAUUAUGGGGUUUCACUUUGUCACCUGGGCUCUCCGGGGUGCAGUGUUGGAAUCGUGGUUCAUUGCAGCCUUGACCUCCCAGGCUCAAGUGAUCCUCCCACCUCAACCUCCCAAGCAGCUGGGACUACAGGUGCAUGCCACCACACCUGGCUAUUUUUUAUUUUUUAUAGAGAUGAGAUCUCCCUGUGUUGCGCAGACUAAUCUUGAACUCCUGGACUCAAGUGAUCCUCCUGCCUUGGCCUCCCAAAGUGUUGGGAUUUCAGGUGUGCCUUGGCCUCCCAAAGUGUUGGGAUUUCAGGUGUGAGCCACUGCAGCCAACCCCUUCUUAGUUCUGGAGAGCAGAGUCUUGCCUGGCAUCCUGGUGCUAUACCAAGAGUCCUCUCCUGGUUUCCAGAGAGGACAUUUGACUUCUUCAGGAGAACUCACCCCACUCCUUUUGGUCCAUUAGGAGCACCAGAAGCUUUGGACCUGAUGGGCUGGGCUUGGUCUCUUCAGAGCCUCUGUCCUCAUUCACAGAGGAGGUAUCAGGUAGGCCUUCCAGCACAGAAUUACAUUACCUGGGAAUUUAAGUGGGAGGAAUUGCAGUGGAGUAUUUUGAAGAUCCUAAGGCAUCCUUCAUUUAAUUUACAUUUUCGAUUCUUCAGAUAUUGGAAUCAAAGAUUGAGACACACACAUAACACUAGAGCACACAGUAGACCAUUUCUACCUUGAGCUAUCUCCUUGUUAGAGAAAAAAUAGUUUUGACUGUUUGUGAUUUUUUACUACGGGCAGAAAAACUUUGAAAAAUUAAUUUCAAUGUAAAAGAGUUUUACUUUUGCCAGAUGAUAACACUUCCUAUGCUAGAACCUGGGGGUACUGGGAUCUGACUUGAAGUAAUUCUAAGUUUAAAUUUAUAGCAACCAUGUGGGUCUGUUCAGCUGGGAGGGGAGAAAUAUUGCGAGCCAUAAGGAUGUAUUUUAGAGAGUUUCUUUAGUAGUCUUCAGAUGUCUACUUGCCCUGUACAAAGUUCAGAAACUGUUUAGGACUUGGAACCUUAGAAUAUCAGAUAGAAAAGGAUUGACAGGCUUAGUCUACUCUGUUUUUGAGAUGCCGAAGCCAGGUGACUUCCCCUAGUGGCAGGUAGGCAAUGUCAGAGUUGUGAUCAUGGCCUGGGGCUCUUUUCCAACCUGCUCUCUGACCUCACAUAGGAUCCGGAUUGAGCAGGGUAAAGGGUGGACCAGUAAAGGCUUUAAUCAGUAAAGUAAUGACAGUGUUUUCCUUCAUUUGAAACCAGUCAGAUUUGAUACUACUUUUCUGUUCAGUUUUUGCCAUCAUUGUUUUCUGGAAGUUUUUAAUCUGUAAUACCUCUUAGUAUGCUUUAACACAUAACACCUAGUGUCAUUGUUAUAGAGAUGAAAGUAGAAAAUUAGCAGGGAUGUAGUAUUUGCCUAUUGCAACUUCUUUUCCUUUAAACCCCUUCCCAUGUCGGGGGGAUACCUUGUGUGUCUGCAGCAUGUGAUGCUGACUCGGACUCUCCAGGCAGCUGACUAACGGCACCUAAACUGCCUGCUGCAUUUUCCCUGCCCCAGCACAGACUUGCUUAGCAGCUCCCGCCUCGGGCCCUCAUUGAGAACCAUCCAGCGGCACAUCAGGCUGGUGCCACUCCCAGUGGCCUUGGCAGUGAGGAGGUGAGGCGAGAGCACCCUCAGGUGCUAGUGGCACGAGUCUUGCCCAGGCUCCCAGGGGAAUGAGUGGUGUGAUGACCUCAUGUGCCAGAAGCCAGGGCAGGCAUGCUUGAGGCUGAGAGAAAGCAACAGAUGGACCUCAGGCAGAAGCAGUCAGAGCAGCCUCAAGGGAGGCUGGUGCGGCACCAGCGUGGCAUCUUCCCAGCAUCUGAAUGUUGGCUUGACCUUCGCUGUUUGUGUGACCUCACCCAAUUCAGUAACCUCACUGAGCCUCCCUUUUUCCAUCUGUGCAACGGUGAUGGUAGUACUUCACUCUGCAAGCGGUGGAGGUGAGAGAUAAUAUAGGUCAAGCAUUUAGCAGUUGGCCAAGCUAAAGACAUAGCUGUUGUUUUUGUUAUUAGAAACACAGCCUCAGCCAGGCACAGUGGCUCACACCAGUAAUUUUAGCACUUUGGGAGGCUGAGGCAGGUGGAUCACUGGAGCUCAGGAGUUCGACACCAGCCUGGGCAACAUAAUGAGACCUAUCUCUACAAAAAAUACAAAAAUUAGCUGGGCGUGGUGGUGUACACCCAUAAUCCCAGCUACACUGGAGGCUUAGUUGAGAGGUUGGCUUGAGCCCAGGAGAUGGAGGUUUCAGUGAGCUGUGAUUGUGCCACUGCACUCUAGCCUGGGUGACAGAGCCAGACUCUGUCUCAAAACAAAAAAACAAAAACAAACAAAAAAAAACAAGAAAAACCAAUACAAUCUCAUUUUUCCUGUUAGGUUAUUCAUACAAACCUGUUGGAAUUUUUUUUCUUUAGGAAUUUGAAUGCUCAUUUUUAAGCCAGACAGUUUCAGGUGGAAGAGAAUCAUGAAAUGCUUUAUCAUGUUUUUGUUAUUUAUCGCUAGAGUAAGACUUAGGAAAGCUAUAGAAAAGAGCCAUCCAGCCAAGAAUUUGAAUUUUGUCAACUUCUCUAUUACAGAGGUUUGCUCAAAGCCCAUAGAGUCUAGAUGAACCUUCUACCUUUGCCCCCAAAAUUGCUUUUUUCUUUUAAUAUGCUAGAUCCCUUUGCUUAUUCCAGGCUGAAAUGAAUGUUAUGUAGCUAGAAGUUUCCUGUCUGUGAUCAAUUCUAAUGGCUUUUGUGAAGGGAAAUGGUUGUAAAUUAUUACCAGUUAAUUAAAUGAGUGUUUCUCUUGAGUCCUUUGUGUAGGCUUUUAUCCAAGCCUGUUUAGAAUCAUGGAACAUUACAGCUAGAAUAUUUUUAGACAACUCUUGUUUCAUGGACAAGGAGACUUAACCAGUGAUAUAAGUACUUGCCUAACUCCUGCAAAGUGAUGCCAAGGAAAAGCAAACUUUGGCUGAGGGUGUAGGAGUGGCUGUGCUGGGGAUCCGGUGGGUACAUCAAGCUAACAGAGUAUAAUUUCUAAGCAGUGAGCCCUUGUCAUCCAUAUGUCACCGGUAUUCCUUGGAGCCAUCUUGGAGUGCUUUUAUUUUUUACAAAGUGCUAUCUUGUAGGACUAUUCUAUAGUAAAUAUUACCUUUCCUAUUUUUAUAGGUGAGGAAAUUGAGGUGGUCAGAUGACCUUAUUUAGCUCUUAGAUCAACUCAGCAGAUAUGUAUUGAGUGUUUACUUGGUUCAAGGAACUCUGCGAGGCUCCUUGGGAACAUAAUGUCAGAUCCUGCUGGAAUGGAGGUUACAGACUUAUUGCAAGUGAUGAGAUAUGUGUAUGAAAAUGUAAGUAAUUGUUCAAGGUAUAGAUAAGUGUUAAUAAUAGUUGAGAUGUGAAUUUUGAGACCGGAGGGAUCAAUGUGAAUAUCAAAUCCUGGCACCAGUUUCUUCCUUCUGCUGCUCAUGAAGCUGUGUCAUCUUCUGUGCUCGGUAACCCAUCCAACCUGUAGCCCUAGGAGCUCCUCUGGGGAGUCUUGAGUACCUUGCAGUUGUCCCGACCCUGGGAGUCAUUCAAUAAAGGUUCAAAUGAAUGAAUAGAUAGGUGCGGUGAAGAGAGACAGGUUUUCCAAGCAGAGAACACGGCAUGAGCAAAUGUGUGGCUGAGUGAUAGAGCCAGGAGAGGGGCCUGACUAGGACAGCAGGUUUUAAAAAGUGAUUUUUUUCUUCUUUUUGUAUUUUAACUUUCUAAAGUGACAAUGGAAGGAAGGGAAUUUUGAAAACAAAGUUUGGAUAGAUUAGUGGGAAGGCAGCAAAAGGGGAGCCCAAGUGGUCCUGAAAGCCAGGUGGAGCAGGGUGUUUUAUUCUGAAGACUCUCGGAGACCAGCGGAGGCUUUAGAGGGGGAAGUUGAUGAGAUCAGCACUUUAGAAAAGGCUGCUUUGUUUUUGGUGGGGUGUUCCAUGACUGCAGGAGAAAGGAUGAGGGAGGAGGCCUGCAGUGACAGGGAUCCUAGAAUGAUGGAGGGAACGAAGGGAAAAACAGAUGGUCACGGUGCCUCAAGUCGGAGUGGCUCCAGGAUUUUAAGCCUGGGAACGCAGAAGAACAGUGGUUCUAGUGAUUCAGUGAUGACCACUGGAAGCUUUAGGAGGAAACAUGGGAUUGGAGCCCUUUAAAGCUGGAAUUGGCCCCUUAGAGAGAAUCUGGCUCAGGCUUCCCAGAUGGUGGUCCGUGGUCUGGCUAUAUCAGAGUUACCUACAGAACUUUUAAAAACAGCAGAUGCCUAGACCCCGUUCCCUUGCCCCAGAAAAUUUAAAAUCAGUAGAUCACCUGUGGGGUCUGGGAAUCUUAUAUUUAAUCCCUUUCUGUGAUUCUUUGGCAAAGAAGAUUGAAUGGCCUUCCUGAUGUCGCAGAUUGGUCAGGACAGAGCACCAGGACCCAGGUCUUCUCUAGCAUUGCUAUUACUCAGCCACAAUGUGGGAGAUAGGGGAUAAGUUCAGAUGGGGAGGUAUAGUAUUUGAGGCAGCGCUGAUUCAUGUGAGUUCAACACUGAUGGCUCUUUGAGGAAGGGGUUACUUGGCAUGAGAACUCAAGGGUUAGAUGGCUCUGAGGGUGCACGUUGGGAAUCAUUCAGUCAAGAAAUGCUUUCCCGAGUGGCUGCUGCAAACCAGGCAUAGGAUAUUUUCAGUCCACUUCGGGGACUCAAAAGUGUAGAACAGAGUAGUAGAAACAACAUAGAGAACCCUAAAGGCUGAAGUUGUGUUUAUGUUUUCUUCUCUGAGCUGUUUUGAGUAAAUUUAGGUGUAAGUUACAAUGUAUGGGUUGAAAUUCAUUAUUUUGGGUAUGGAUGUCCCGUUGUUCUAGCACCAUUUGUUGACACUGAGUUUUUAUACUUUUGUUCAUUUGUCUAUUUGUAUAGAAGAAUCACAUUUUUUUAAAGACCACUGUUAUCUGGGUUUCAACAAGGGCCCAGGAGUUGUUCUUUUUACCAAGAGAAGUGGUCUGUAGGGGAGGGGGUUAGUGUGUUUAUUGCUCCUUGAAUGACUGUUAUAGUAAGAAUGCUAAGUGUGUUCAUUUCUAUGUGGGGCUGCCCUAGACUCUGACCUCAGCUCUGUUCUAUUAGACACUCUGUCAGUGCAUUAGCCAAUGACAUAGGUAGCCUGAGGCCCUGAUUUGGGGAGCCAUAAAACUGAGAAGGGGAGUGAAUGAACUGACUGGAUUUGCGAUCCAGUGAACGCUAUGACCUGGGACAAGCCAAAAUAUUGCAGAAAAAAAAAAUGAAGCACUUAGGUUUUUAUGAAGGUUUUGAGCCUAACCACUGCACGAGCACAGGAUGUGGGAAGCAAAGCCUUAUGGCAGCUAGAAAAGAUGCAGAGGUUUUAGUUCAUUGCAAGCUCAGCCUGGGUCACUGGGGCUUCUCAGAGCGCCCAUGUAUUCUCGCUGCAUUGGUAAAGGGCACUGUCACUGUCAAGAUCAACGUUAAUGAUAAUCUUGCUCUUGCUGGUGAAAGUCAGGUCACACACUCAGCCUGACUUCACCCUUUAAUGGGGGUGUGAAGAAAUUGGGGCAUGUCAGGAGGAAACUGACUAGAAUGGUGAAGGAGGAGAAAAUCAUGUCCUACAUGAAGUUGCUGAGAGUUUGAGAUACCCAGGUCUAUUUUAUUUACUCAUUUGUUCCACAAACCAUUUUCUGUCCCCUUAUAUGCAAGGUAGGGUCUCCUUUGGGGACAGGGCAUAAUGACUACAACAUGAUGUGGGUUCCAGCAGUAGUCUUCAUAACAGGUGUGGAGUUGCCCACCUGUCUGAAAGAGGUCUGGAAAGGUCCCCCUAUACAGGUGGGUCUUGAAUUGAUGGACAAAUAGGAGUUGGACAAGUAUAAAAAGGAAGAAAGGAGUUUCCAGCCAGAAAGAUCACAUACCCCAAAUCACUAGGCAAUAAGCUACAGAUGGGUAAUGUGUAAUUUUCAUAAUUUUGACUAUAUUCCCCAGUAUGCUGCUUGAUCCAUAAUGCGUUUGGUUGCUCUCUCAGAAUAAAUGAAAUAACAUACCUCCCUGGAGAGUGUACAAGAAUUAAGAGAUGGGGAUACUGGUUGUAUGCAGCUGCAGUGGUGGGAAGAGCUUAGGCUGAAAGGUAGGAAGGGGUUUAGUGUCUAGGGCUAUGUGCUGUGCUAAAGAAUUUGGACCUUAUCAUGGACAGGAGAGGAAACACUGACGGUUUCUAAGUUAGGAAGCCACAUGGUCAGAUUUUAAUUUUUGAAACAUGUCACUGGCAGCAGCUGGAGGACAGUAGUCUGGAAAUAGAAGGCAGCUAGAAGCCCGUUCAGGGAGGCCAGAUGAACCACGGCAGUAGGAGUGGAGCAGGGGUAGAUCCAGGAGAGACUUCGAGAGUGGACGUGUUGGGAUCUGAGAGCGAUUCAAUGUACCUGCUGAGGAGCUGGGCUUCUGGCGUGGCCUACUGGGUGGAUCUCGAGCCAGAGGGGAAAGUAUUUGUGGUAAUAACCCUUACCGGGAGUUUCACUGAAGCUACUCUCCAGAGAGACCGGAUCUUCAAACAUUUUACCAGGAAGCGCCAAAGGGCUAUGCGAAGGCGAGUCCACCAGAUCAAUGGACACAAGUUCAUGGCCACGUAUCUGAGGCAGCCCACCUACUGCUCUCACUGCAGGGAGUUUAUCUGGGGAGUGUUUGGGAAACAGGGUUAUCAGUGCCAAGUGUGCACCUGUGUCGUCCAUAAACGCUGCCAUCAUCUAAUUGUUACAGCCUGUACUUGCCAAAACAAUAUUAACAAAGUGGAUUCAAAGAUUGCAGAACAGAGGUUCGGGAUCAACAUCCCACACAAGUUCAGCAUCCACAACUACAAAGUGCCAACAUUCUGCGAUCACUGUGGCUCACUGCUCUGGGGAAUAAUGCGACAAGGACUUCAGUGUAAAAUAUGUAAAAUGAAUGUGCAUAUUCGAUGUCAAGCGAACGUGGCCCCUAACUGUGGGGUAAAUGCGGUGGAACUUGCCAAGACCCUGGCAGGGAUGGGUCUCCAACCCGGAAAUAUUUCUCCAACCUCGAAACUCGUUUCCAGAUCGACCCUAAGACGACAGGGAAAGGAGAGCAGCAAAGAAGGAAAUGGGAUUGGGGUUAAUUCUUCCAACCGACUUGGUAUCGACAACUUUGAGUUCAUCCGAGUGUUGGGGAAGGGGAGUUUUGGGAAGGUGAUGCUUGCAAGAGUAAAAGAAACAGGAGACCUCUAUGCUGUGAAGGUGCUGAAGAAGGACGUGAUUCUGCAGGAUGAUGAUGUGGAAUGCACCAUGACCGAGAAAAGGAUCCUGUCUCUGGCCCGCAAUCACCCCUUCCUCACUCAGUUGUUCUGCUGCUUUCAGACCCCCGAUCGUCUGUUUUUUGUGAUGGAGUUUGUGAAUGGGGGUGACUUGAUGUUCCACAUUCAGAAGUCUCGUCGUUUUGAUGAAGCACGAGCUCGCUUCUAUGCUGCAGAAAUCAUUUCGGCUCUCAUGUUCCUCCAUGAUAAAGGAAUCAUCUAUAGAGAUCUGAAACUGGACAAUGUCCUGUUGGACCACGAGGGUCACUGUAAACUGGCAGACUUCGGAAUGUGCAAGGAGGGGAUUUGCAAUGGUGUCACCACGGCCACAUUCUGUGGCACGCCAGACUAUAUCGCUCCAGAGAUCCUCCAGGAAAUGCUGUACGGGCCUGCAGUAGACUGGUGGGCAAUGGGCGUGUUGCUCUAUGAGAUGCUCUGUGGUCACGCGCCUUUUGAGGCAGAGAACGAAGAUGACCUCUUUGAGGCCAUACUGAAUGAUGAGGUGGUCUACCCUACCUGGCUCCAUGAAGAUGCCACAGGGAUCCUAAAAUCUUUCAUGACCAAGAACCCCACCAUGCGCUUGGGCAGCCUGACUCAGGGAGGCGAGCACGCCAUCUUGAGACAUCCUUUUUUUAAGGAAAUCGACUGGGCCCAGCUGAACCAUCGCCAAAUAGAACCGCCUUUCAGACCCAGAAUCAAAUCCCGAGAAGAUGUCAGUAAUUUUGACCCUGACUUCAUAAAGGAAGAGCCAGUUUUAACUCCAAUUGAUGAGGGACAUCUUCCAAUGAUUAACCAGGAUGAGUUUAGAAACUUUUCCUAUGUGUCUCCAGAAUUGCAACCAUAGCCUUAUGGGGAGUGAGAGAGAGGGCACGAGAACCCAAAGGGAAUAGAGAUUCUCCAGGAAUUUCCUCUAUGGGACCUUCCCAGCAUCAGCCUUAGAACAAGAACCUUACCUUCAAGGAGCAAGUGAAGAACUCUGUGAAGGAUGGAACUUUCAGAUAUCAACUAUUUAGAGUCCAGAGGGAGCCAUGGCACUAGAAAUAGUUGAUAAUGAAAUGAGAUUUUAUGAAGUAUACCGCUCCACCUAUGAGCGUCUGUCUCUGUGGGCUUGGGAUGUUAACAGGAGCCAAAAGGAGGGAAAGUGUGAAGAAUAAAGUAGAUCUGAGAAAUUCUGAGCCAAUCAGGCUUCUUAAUUCAAGAGACAAACCAAGACGUUCUGUCAACUGUGCUGUGCUCUUCUUUAAGCCAAUGAACCCCAAUUCCUGGCAGUCUACAAGAAGUCUCUUAAUGCUAAUGAAGAAUUUAAAGGUCUUUUUAAGGAAAUGAAGGGCUUUCCAAAUAGAAUGAUUUACUCUGAAGAAACAAACAAUGGUAUCUCUGAAACUCACAACCUAAAGCCCAAUCUUGAAAAUAUGUUGUGCACCAAGACGACUGCUUCAGCUUCUUCUCUUAUCCUUACUUUCUUUAAUAGAUAUUUAUUAAACUGUCCAGUGAAAAGGUGCCACAAUGCCCAGUAUUGUAAACAACAGGUUUGCAUUCAUGAAGCUUUCAUUCAUUCUGGAGUCUACUAAUUUACCUGAAUGGUGUUUGCAUUCUGUGAAAUGCCUCUCCACGUUGCAUAUGUCACACUUUUGUCUGCACAUAACUCUUUUUUCACAAGAAGGGUCACUGCCACAACAGCACAGUCAGCGGGUGAAUUACAGGUGCCUGCUGCCUGCCUACCUGGGUAAUCUGAUCUUGUCUGUAUCGCCGUGUGCUCAUCACUGAAGAAUUGCAGGCCACUCAUGUCAGUGACCAGAUUUGUGGCUUAUAAACAUUAGCAGUUUAUUUAUGUUUUAAGAUGCAAAGAUGUGUGUUUGAUAUUCACUUUAAUAAUUAGAAAUGGAUCUUGUAAACAGGGCAUAUAUCAAAGAUGACCUUAUAAUAUGUACCCGAAUAUACAGUUCAAGAAUUUUGUCUGACUGGAAAUAAAUGCAUUUUGUAGCAAAA